AGCUCCAAUUGCUCUAUGUUUAGAAUUGCCUCUUUUUCAAGAUGGAUUUCCUUCACAGGAAUGGAGUGCUCAUAAUUCAGCAUUUGCAGAAGGACUACCGAGCUUACUACACUUUUCUAAAUUUUAUGUCCAAUGUUGGAGACCCCAGGAAUAUCUUUUUCAUUUAUUUUCCACUUUGUUUUCAAUUUAAUCAGACAGUUGGAACCAAGAUGAUAUGGGUAGCAGUCAUUGGGGAUUGGUUAAAUCUUAUAUUUAAAUGGAUAUUAUUUGGUCAUCGACCUUACUGGUGGGUCCAAGAAACUCAGAUUUACCCAAAUCACUCAAGUCCAUGCCUUGAACAGUUCCCUACUACAUGUGAAACAGGUCCAGGAAGUCCAUCUGGCCAUGCAAUGGGCGCAUCCUGUGUCUGGUAUGUCAUGGUAACCGCUGCCCUGAGCCACACUGUCUGUGGGAUGGAUAAGUUCUCUAUCACUCUGCACAGACUGACCUGGUCAUUUCUUUGGAGUGUUUUUUGGUUGAUUCAAAUCAGUGUCUGCAUCUCCAGAGUAUUCAUAGCAACACAUUUUCCUCAUCAAGUUAUUCUUGGAGUAAUUGGUGGCAUGCUGGUGGCAGAGGCCUUUGAACACACUCCAGGCAUCCAAACGGCCAGUCUGGGCACAUACCUGAAGACCAACCUCUUUCUCUUCCUGUUUGCAGUUGGCUUUUACCUGCUUCUUAGGGUGCUCAACAUUGACCUGCUGUGGUCCGUGCCCAUAGCCAAAAAGUGGUGUGCUAACCCCGACUGGAUCCACAUUGACACCACGCCUUUUGCUGGACUCGUGAGAAACCUUGGGGUCCUCUUUGGCUUGGGCUUUGCAAUCAACUCAGAGAUGUUCCUCCUGAGCUGCCGAGGGGGAAAUAACUACACACUGAGCUUCCGGUUGCUCUGUGCCUUGACCUCAUUGACAAUACUGCAGCUCUACCAUUUCCUCCAGAUCCCGACUCACGAAGAGCAUUUAUUUUAUGUGCUGUCUUUUUGUAAAAGUGCAUCCAUUCCCCUAACUGUGGUUGCUUUCAUUCCCUACUCUGUUCAUAUGUUAAUGAAACAAAGCGGAAAGAAGAGUCAGUAGAGUGGUGCCUAGAGUUAGUGCUCUGUGUCACAGAUCACCCUUCUCCAUCCACCAGUAGAGCCACAGAGUAGGCACAGACCAGAGGCUUCUAAUCCGACUUCACAGAAUAGCGGCACAGGCCCCAUUCCCCAUAGAGAUGUUUAGUUUGGCCUUCGCACUGGUCUUUUUUUUUAAUCCUUCAGUUACCAAUAUUUAGAUACAAGAAUAUUUGACAUAAAAAUCGGAAGUUCUGUAUUUCUUGAAAAAUCUGAUAGUAUGACAACACAGAGCCUGCAUCCCCAGCUGGAGACAACUGACCAGAGCUGCAUACUAACAGUCCCCAGUAGGAGGCAAGGACUCCAUUUUCUCACAGUCUUCAGCAUCCCAGCAGGAGCCCCACUAUGAUUCCUUUAUCUUCUUAAGGCCAGGCUGCAUCUGAUUCCUGUUGACAUUUUAGUGGGGACCACAGCCAUAUCCAGUUUCAGUUUUCAGAUGAGGAAAUGGAAGCCUAUUUAGGUAAAAGAACUUGCCUGGAGUCACGCCACCUUCAGAGCAGGAAUUAGAACCCAAGGCUUCUGACACAUAUCCCCAUUACACUGUGUGUUUGAGUGUGCACACAUGCACAUGCUUUUUGUUUGUAUGUUUCCUUUUUAGAACCAGGGACUUGCUCUGUUGCCCAGGCUGGAGUGCAGUGGUGGAUAGCGGCUCACUGCAGCCUCAAACUCCUGGCUCAAAUGAUCCUCCCUCCUCAGCCUCCCAUUAGCUAAGACUACAGGUGUGCACCACCAUGCCUGGCUAAUUUUUGAAUAUUUUUUAGAGCCAGCUUCUUACUAUAUUUGCCCAGGCUGGUCUUGAACUCCUGGCCUCAAGGAGUUCCCUUGAGGAUGUUCCACCCAUGUCAGCCUCCCACAGUGCUGGGAUUGCAGGCUUGAGCCAUUGUAUUAAUAGUUGGCCUACACUGUCUUUUGUUUCUUCAUUUACAAGAGGUAAAAAUCAGUAAGAAUGAAUGCUUUCAUUUAGAUUCUAUGAUGACUGCCAUAUAAAUCAGCUACCUUUUCAGAAAUGACAUUGAAAUACUGCAUCCUCUUUGACUUAUACCCCACACAUACAUGCAGGGUCUAGGUGGGACCAACAGUGGCUCCAGAUGUAUAUACACACGGGUCCAGGGACAACAGAACAGGCCAGGCUACAGUAUGGACUUGAACCUCUGCUUCACUUCUGGUCUCUGUUUUACAGUAGUGCUCACCAAUAUUUCAAUAAAUUCUACUGAACUUACUCUAAUAGAACAUUAUUCAACCCCCAAAGACUUAUCUCUUCACUAUGACAUCUCCAUACUUUAUUUUUAGGAGACAGACUUUCAAAACCAGAGAAAUCAGGUGCCUUCCUCAAGGUCAUGCUCCAACCCAGGCCAACUAUUAAAUGCUUGCAUCUGUUAGCUGGAUUAGUCUCUAUGUAUACUGAACUGUGAUGAAAAUCUAUAGCUUUGUUUUAGAAAAUUAUUGUUGAUGGACUAUUAAUAUUAUAUUAACAAUUUCUCAGUAAGUGUGUUUUUUCCUCAUUGAAUCUAGGAAUGCUGGGCUUUAAGUUGAUAACUGUGUCAUUUCAAUCAAGUACAAGGAUUUUGAGGCAGAUUUUGCUAGAUAUCUUAGUAAUCCCCCACAAUGUUUUAUGUAACUCUUCUCAGAAUAUCAAUACAUUAAUUAUUUUAGAUGACAUAUUAAAUAAUCUAUGAAUAUUAAUGAAAACAAUACAGUUGAAGUGAGUGUUGUUUAACAUGAUAGUAGCUGAGGAUAACAAACCUCAAAAAAUCAAAGUAUUAAUUACUCCUUUCCAAGUAUAUGUAUAGAGCAUGUGUCAUUGCUUUUAUAAAACGCACUUAAUAGCUUUCUUUCUAAAAGGCAACUGAACUUUCUAAAAGGUAAAUAAACUGAACUUGAUAUUA